GCAGCGUAGCAAAUCCAGGCAGCGCCACGCGCGGCCGGGGCCGGGCGGAACCGAGAAGCCGGGACCGCGCUGCGACGCGCCGGCCGCAUGGAGCCUGCCGCCGGUUUCCUGUCUCCGCGCCCCUUCCAGCGUGCGGCCGCCGCGCCCGCUCCCCCGGCCGGGCCCGGGCCGCCUCCGAGUGCCUUGCGCGGACCUGAGCUGGAGAUGCUGGCCGGGCUACCGACGUCAGACCCCGGGCGCCUCAUCACGGACCCGCGCAGCGGCCGCACCUACCUCAAAGGCCGCUUGUUGGGCAAGGGGGGCUUCGCCCGCUGCUACGAGGCCACUGACACAGAGACUGGCAGCGCCUACGCUGUCAAAGUCAUCCCGCAGAGCCGCGUCGCCAAGCCGCAUCAGCGCGAGAAGAUCCUAAAUGAGAUUGAGCUGCACCGAGACCUGCAGCACCGCCACAUCGUGCGUUUUUCGCACCACUUUGAGGACGCUGACAACAUCUACAUUUUCUUGGAGCUCUGCAGCCGAAAGUCCCUGGCCCACAUCUGGAAGGCCCGGCACACCCUGUUGGAGCCAGAAGUGCGCUACUACCUGCGGCAGAUCCUUUCUGGCCUCAAGUACUUGCACCAGCGCGGCAUCUUGCACCGGGACCUCAAGUUGGGAAAUUUUUUCAUCACUGAGAACAUGGAACUGAAGGUGGGGGAUUUUGGGCUGGCAGCCCGGUUGGAGCCUCCGGAGCAGAGGAAGAAGACCAUCUGUGGCACCCCCAACUAUGUGGCUCCAGAAGUGCUGCUGAGACAGGGCCACGGCCCUGAGGCGGAUGUAUGGUCACUGGGCUGUGUCAUGUACACGCUGCUCUGCGGGAGCCCUCCCUUUGAGACGGCUGACCUGAAGGAGACGUACCGCUGCAUCAAGCAGGUUCACUACACGCUGCCUGCCAGCCUCUCACUGCCUGCCCGGCAGCUCCUGGCCGCCAUCCUUCGGGCCUCACCCCGAGACCGCCCCUCUAUUGACCAGAUCCUGCGCCAUGACUUCUUUACCAAGGGCUACACCCCCGAUCGACUCCCUAUCAGCAGCUGCGUGACAGUCCCAGACCUGACACCCCCCAACCCAGCUAGGAGUCUGUUUGCCAAAGUUACCAAGAGCCUCUUUGGCAGAAAGAAGAAGAGUAAGAAUCAUGCCCAGGAGAGGGAUGAGGUCUCCGGUUUGGUGAGCGGCCUCAUGCGCACAUCCGUUGGCCAUCAGGAUGCCAGGCCAGAGGCUCCAGCAGCUUCUGGCCCAGCCCCUGUCAGCCUGGUAGAGACAGCACCUGAAGACAGCUCACCCCGUGGGACACUGGCAAGCAGUGGAGAUGGAUUUGAAGAAGGUCUGACUGUGGCCACAGUAGUGGAGUCAGCCCUUUGUGCUCUGAGAAAUUGUAUAGCCUUCAUGCCCCCAGCGGAACAGAACCCGGCCCCCCUGGCCCAGCCAGAGCCUCUGGUGUGGGUCAGCAAGUGGGUUGACUACUCCAAUAAGUUCGGCUUUGGGUAUCAACUGUCCAGCCGCCGUGUGGCUGUGCUCUUCAACGAUGGCACACAUAUGGCCCUGUCGGCCAACAGAAAGACUGUGCACUACAAUCCCACCAGCACAAAGCACUUCUCCUUCUCCGUGGGUGCUGUGCCCCGGGCCCUGCAGCCUCAGCUGGGUAUCCUGCGGUACUUCGCCUCCUACAUGGAGCAGCACCUCAUGAAGGGUGGAGAUCUGCCCAGUGUGGAAGAGGUAGAGGUACCUGCUCCGCCCUUGCUGCUGCAGUGGGUCAAGACGGAUCAGGCUCUCCUCAUGCUGUUUAGUGAUGGCACUGUCCAGGUGAACUUCUACGGGGACCACACCAAGCUGAUUCUCAGUGGCUGGGAGCCCCUCCUUGUGACUUUUGUGGCCCGAAAUCGUAGUGCUUGUACUUACCUCGCUUCCCACCUUCGGCAGCUGGGCUGCUCUCCAGACCUGCGGCAGCGACUCCGCUAUGCUCUGCGCCUGCUCCGGGACCGCAGCCCAGCCUAGGACCCAAGCCCUGAGGCCUGAGGCCUGUGCCUGUCAGGCUCUGGCCCUUGCCUUUGUGGCCUUCCCCCUUCCUUUGGUGCCUCACUGGGGGCUUUGGGCCGAAUCCCCCAGGGAAUCAGGGACCAGCUUUACUGGAGUUGGGGGCGGCUUGUCUUCGCUGGCUCCUACCCCAUCUCCAAGAUAAGCCUGAGCCUUAGCUCCCAGCUAGGGGGCGUUAUUUAUGGACCACUUUUAUUUAUUGUCAGACACUUAUUUAUUGGGAUGUGAGCCCCAGGGGGGCCUCCUCCUAGGAUAAUAAACAAUUUUGCAGAA